CCCCCGGCUCGCCUGCCCGCCAUGGCCGACAAGGAAGCAGCCUUUGACAACACAGUGGAAGAAUGAGUGAUCAACAAGGAAUACAAAAUAUGGAAAAAGAACACCCCUUUUCUUUAUAAUUUGGUGAUGACCCAUGCUCUGGAGUGGCCCAGCCUAACUGCCCAGUGGCUUCCAGAUGUAACCAGACCAGAAGGGAAAGAUUUCAGCCUUCAUCGACUUGUCCUGGGGACACACACAUCGGAUGAACAAAACCAUCUUGUUAUAGCCAGUGUGCAGCUGCCUGAUGAUGAUGCUCAGUUUGAUGCAUCACACUACGACAGAGAGAAAGGAGAAUUUGGAGGUUUUGGUUCAGUUAGUGGAAAAAUUGAAAUAGAAAUCAAGAUCAACCAUGAAGGAAAAGUAAACAGGGCCCGUUAUAUGCCCCAGAACCCUUGUAUCAUCACAACAAAGACUCCUUCCAGUGAUAUUCUUGUCUUUGACUAUACAAAACAUCCUUCUAAACCAGAUCCUUCUGGAGAAUGCAACCCAGACUUGCGUCUCCGUGGACAUCAGAAGGAAGGCUAUGGGCUUUCUUGGAACCUAAAUCUCAGUGGGCACUUACUUAGUGCUUCAGAUGACCACACCAUCUGCCUGUGGGACAUCAGUGCCGUUCCAAAGGAGGGAAAAGUGGUAGAUGCGAAGACCAUCUUUACAGGGCAUACGGCAAUAGUAGAAGAUGUUUCCUGGCAUCUACUCUGUGAGUCUCUGUUUGGGUCAGUUGCUGAUGAUCAGAAACUGAUGAUUUGGGAUACUCGUUCAAACAAUACUUCCAAACCAAGCCACUCAGUUGACACUCACACUGCUGAAGUGAACUGCCUUUCUUUCAGUCCUUAUAGUGAGUUCAUUCUUGCCACAGGAUCAGCUGACAAGACUGUUGCCUUGUGGGAUCUGAGAAAUCUGAAACUUAAGUUGCAUUCCUUUGAGUCACAUAAGGAUGAAAUAUUCCAGGUUCAGUGGUCACCUCACAAUGAGACUAUUUUAGCUUCCAGUGGUACUGAUCACAGACCGAAUGUCUAGGAUUUAAGUAAAAUUGGAGAGGAACAAUCCCCAGAAGAUGCAGAAGACAGGCCACCAGAGUUGUUGUUUAUUCAUGGUGGUCACACUGCCAAGAUACCUGAUUUCUCCUGGAAUCCCAGUGAACCUUGAGUGAUGUGUUCUGUAUCGGAAGACAAUAUCAUGCAAGUGUGGCAAAUGGCAGAGAACAUUUAUAAUGAUGAAGACCCUGAAGGAAGCAUGGAUCCAGAAGGACAAGGGUCCUAAAUAUGUCUUUACUUCUUGUGAUUUUAGACUCCCCUUUUUUCUUCUCAACCCCGAGAGUGAUUUAACACUGGUUCUGAGACAGAUUUUAUUCAGCUAUCCCUCUAUAUAAUAGGUACCACCGAUAAUGCUAUUAGCCCAAACAGUGGGUGUUUUCUAAAUAUUAAUGGGGGGCUUGAUUCAACAAAGCUACAGAGUUAUGUUGAAAUUUUCUUCAGGAAUUUUCUAGUAACCCAGGUCUAAAGUAGCUACAGAAAGGGGAAUAUUAUGUGUGAUUAUUUUUCUUCUUAUGCUAUAUCCCCAAGUUUUUUGGACUCAUUUAAGUAAAGGCUAGAGUGAGUAAGGAGAAUAGAGCCAAAUGAGGUAGGUGUCUGAGCCAUGAAGUAUAAAUACUGAAAGAUGUCACUUUUAUUCAGGAAAUAGGGGAGAUUCAAGUCAUAUAGAUUCCUACUCGAAAAUCUCGACACCUGAGUUUCCAGGAUGCACAUUUUCAUACGUAGACCAGUUUCCUCUUGGUUUCUUCAGUUAAGUCAAAACAGCACGUUCCUCUUUCCCCAUAUAUUCAUAUAUUUUUGCUCGUUAGUGUAUUUCUUGAGCUGUUUUCAUGUUGUUUAUUUCCUGUCUGUGAAAUGGUGUUUUUUUUUUUUUUGUUGGUGUGUGUUUUUUUUUUUUAACUUGGGACCGCCAAGUUGUAAAGAUGUAUGUUUUUACCUGACAGGUAUACCACAGGUAGAUUGUCAAGUUGAGAAGAGUGAAUCGAUAAAUUGUAUUUGUUUUAAAAAUUAAAUUAAUCCUUGAUAAGAGUUGCUUUUUUUUUAGGAGUUUGUCCUUGACCACUAGUUUGAUGCCAUCUCCAUUUUGGGUGACCUGUUUCACCAGCAGGCCUAUUACUCUCCAUGACUAACUGUGCCUUGAACCGGGGCAUUGCUGCUGUCAAGGAGGAUGCAGUCGAGAUGCUGGCCAGCUACGGGCUGGCGUACUCCCUCAUGAAGUUCUUCACGGGUCCCAUGAGUGACUUCAAAAAUGUGGGCCUGGUGUUUGUGAACAGCAAGAGAGACAGGACCAAAGCCGUCCUGUGUAUGGUGGUGGCAGGGGCCAUCGCUGCCGUCUUUCACACACUGAUAGCUUAUAGUGAUUUAGGAUACUACAUUAUCAAUAAACUGCACCAUGUGGACGAGUCGGUGGGGAGCAAGACGAGAAGGGCCUUCCUGUACCUCGCCGCCUUUCCUUUCAUGGACGCAAUGGCAUGGACCCAUGCUGGCAUUCUCUUAAAACACAAAUACAGUUUCCUGGUGGGAUGUGCCUCAAUCUCAGAUGUCAUAGCUCAGGUUGUUUUUGUAGCCAUUUUGCUUCACAGUCACCUGGAAUGCCGGGAGCCCCUGCUCAUCCCGAUCCUCUCCUUGUACAUGGGCGCACUUGUGCGCUGCACCACCCUGUGCCUGGGCUACUACAAGAACAUUCACGACAUCAUCCCUGACAGAAGUGGCCCGGAGCUGGGGGGAGAUGCAACAAUAAGAAAGAUGCUGAGCUUCUGGUGGCCUUUGGCUCUAAUUCUGGCCACACAGAGAAUCAGUCGGCCUAUUGUCAACCUCUUUGUUUCCCGGGACCUUGGUGGCAGUUCUGCAGCCACAGAGGCAGUGGCGAUUUUGACAGCCACAUACCCUGUGGGUCACAUGCCAUACGGCUGGUUGACGGAAAUCCGUGCUGUGUAUCCUGCUUUCGACAAGAAUAACCCCAGCAACAAACUGGUGAGCACGAGCAACACAGUCACGGCAGCCCACAUCAAGAAGUUCACCUUCGUCUGCAUGGCUCUGUCACUCACGCUCUGUUUCGUGAUGUUUUGGACACCCAACGUGUCUGAGAAAAUCUUGAUAGACAUCAUCGGAGUGGACUUUGCCUUUGCAGAACUCUGUGUUGUUCCUUUGCGGAUCUUCUCCUUCUUCCCAGUUCCAGUCACAGUGAGGGCGCAUCUCACCGGGUGGCUGAUGACACUGAAGAAAACCUUCGUCCUUGCCCCCAGCUCUGUGCUGCGGAUCAUCGUCCUCAUCGCCAGCCUCGUGGUCCUACCCUACCUGGGGGUGCACGGUGCGACCCUGGGCGUGGGCUCCCUCCUGGCGGGCUUUGUGGGAGAAUCCACCAUGGUCGCCAUCGCUGCGUGCUAUGUCUACCGGAAGCAGAAAAAGAAGAUGGAGAAUGAGUCGGCCACGGAGGGGGAAGACUCUGCCAUGACAGACAUGCCUCCGACAGAGGAGGUGACAGACAUCGUGGAAAUGAGAGAGGAGAAUGAAUAAGGCACGGGACGCCAUGGGCACUGCAGGGACAGUCAGUCAGGAUGACACUUCGGCAUCAUCUCUUCCCUCUCCCAUCGUAUUUUGUUCCCUUUUUUUUGUUUUGUUUUGGUAAUGAAAGAGGCCUUGAUUUAAAGGUUUCGUGUCAAUUCUCUAGCAUACUGGGUAUGCUCACACUGACGGGGGGACCUAGUGAAUGGUCUUUACUGUUGCUAUGUAAAAACAAACGAAACAACUGACUUCAUACCCCUGCCUCACGAAAACCCAAAAGACACAGCUGCCUCACGGUUGACGUUGUGUCCUCCUCCCCUGGACAAUCUCCUCUUGGAACCAAAGGACUGCAGCUGUGCCAUCGCGCCUCGGUCACCCUGCACAGCAGGCCACAGACUCUCCUGUCCCCCUUCAUCGCUCUUAAGAAUCAACAGGUUAAAACUCGGCUUCCUUUGAUUUGCUUCCCAGUCACAUGGCCGUACAAAGAGAUGGAGCCCCGGUGGCCUCUUAAAUUUCCCUUCCGCCACGGAGUUCGAAACCAUCUACUCCACACAUGCAGGAGGCGGGUGGCACGCUGCAGCCCGGAGUCCCCGUUCACACUGAGGAACGGAGACCUGUGACCACAGCAGGCUGACAGAUGGACAGAAUCUCCCGUAGAAAGGUUUGGUUUGAAAUGCCCCGGGGGCAGCAAACUGACAUGGUUGAAUGAUAGCAUUUCACUCUGCGUUCUCCUAGAUCUGAGCAAGCUGUCAGUUCUCACCCCCACCGUGUAUAUACAUGAGCUAACUUUUUUAAAUUGUCACAAAAGCGCAUCUCCAGAUUCCAGACCCUGCCGCAUGACUUUUCCUGAAGGCUUGCUUUUCCCUCGCCUUUCCUGAAGGUCGCAUUAGAGCGAGUCACAUGGAGCAUCCUAACUUUGCAUUUUAGUUUUUACAGUGAACUGAAGCUUUAAGUCUCAUCCAGCAUUCUAAUGCCAGGUUGCUGUAGGGUAACUUUUGAAGUAGAUAUAUUACCUGGUUCUGCUAUCCUUAGUCAUAACUCUGCGGUACAGGUAAUUGAGAAUGUACUACGGUACUUCCCUCCCACACCAUACGAUAAAGCAAGACAUUUUAUAACGAUACCAGAGUCACUAUGUGGUCCUCCCUGAAAUAACGCAUUCGAAAUCCAUGCAGUGCAGUAUAUUUUUCUAAGUUUUGGAAAGCAGGUUUUUUCCUUUAAAAAAAUUAUAGACACGGUUCACUAAAUUGAUUUAGUCAGAAUUCCUAGACUGAAAGAACCUAAAAAAAAAAAUAUUUUAAAGAUAUAAAUAUAUGCUGUAUAUGUUAUGUAAUUUAUUUUAGGCUAUAAUACAUUUCCUAUUUUCGCAUUUUCAAUAAAAUGUCUCUAAUACAAUACGGUGAUUGCUUGUGUGCUCAACAUACCUGCAGUUGAAACGUAUUGUAUCAAUGAACAUUGUACCUUAUUGGCAGCAGUUUUAUAAAGUCCGUCAUUUGCAUUUGAAUGUAAGGCUCAGUAAAUGACAGAACUAUUUUUCAUUAUGGGUAACUGGGGAAUAAAUGGGUCACUGGAGUAGGAAUAGAAGUGCAAGCUGGAAAGGCAAAAAUGAGAAAGAAAAAGGCAGGCCCUUUGUGUCUACCGUUUUCAGUGCUGUGUGAUCAUAUUGUUCCUCACAGCAAAAAAGAAUGCAAGGGCAUAAUGUUAGCUGUGAACAUGCCAGGGUUGCAUUCACAUUCCUGGGUACCCAGUGCUGAUGGGGUGUGCCCACGUGGGGACAUGUCCUUGGCGUGCUUCCUCAGAGUGGCUUUUCCUCCAUUAAUACAUAUAUGAGUACUGAAAAAUUAAGUUGCAUAGCUGCUUUGCAGUGGUUUCAGAGGCAGAUCUGAGAAGAUUAAAAAAAAAUCUCAAUGUAUCAGCUUUUUUUAAAGGACAUUACUAGAAAAUUAAACAGUAUUUUUUAACAUGUGUGACUUUCAUGCUUCUGGGGUUGGAGCUUAAAGAUCCAAACUGAGAAAGCAGGCCGGGCAUGGUGGCUCAUGCCUGUAAUCCCAACACUUUGGGAGGCCAAGGAGGGUGGAUCACUUAAGGUCAGGAGUUUGAGACCAGCCUGGCCAACAUGGCAAAACCCUGUCUCUACUAAAAACAUAAAAAUUAGCUGGGGGUGGUAGCACAUACCUGUAAUCCCAGCUACUCAGGAGGCUGAGGCAGGAGAAUUUGCUUGAUCCUGGGAGGCAGAGGUUGUAGUGAGCCGAGAUCGCGCCAUCGCACUCCAGCCUGGGUGACAAGAGCAAAACUCCAUCUCAAAAAAAAAAAAAAUCCUUUCCCUCUAAAUCCAGGAAGGAUCAGCAAGGGCCUCCUCAUUAUGAGAUGAGGAAAUACAACUCCAGAGAUUCCUUCAGUGAUCAAGAUCAGUGGGCCAUAAUAUUUGGUUAGAGUUUCUGAGAACACAGGAAGCAAUGCCACACUCAGGCCACCACAAUGGAGCUGAUUUGGCAGGACUUGUUCAAACCUUUCACCUUAAAGCACGUGAUCCUUCUUCGUACAUUUUCUUCACUUGGGCUGCUUAAGUCACAGCCUAACAACUUUGAGGCAAAACUGAGAACUGGCAUAUUCUCCUGCGUUUCUUCUAAUCGAGUCCCAUCAUCCAGCUAGACAUGAGAGAUCAAACCAGGGAGGGUGACCUUUCUCCUUCCCACUUUUCAGAGUCAUUGGGGCAACUUUUUGACUUUUGUGACCAAAGAAACAUUCCCCCAAAACAUUUAUUUUUCAUUGUAGGGCAUUCAGCUGACAGCUGCAUUUUAGAAAGUUACCAUGCCUGUGAGAUUCUCAUGUCAAAGACCAGGGAAAGACCAGGUGUGACUUUCUCCAAAACUGAGUGAUUGCUUGUGGAUGAAUACAAUCUAAAAAUACAAGGCCAUGAAGUAGUUUUUCAUUUAGAUGCUGAGAAAUAAUAGGUUUGGGCAGCUCAAAGCAUAGGAAAUAGUAAGGGUUUUCUAGAGCUCCUCCUUUGGUGGCCUGUUUGAGUAGCACAAGGGACGUCAUCCUAAAUGUGCAGUUGCCAUUUGUUCUGUAGUGACUUACAGGGAUCUCAGUGGCAAAGGGCGUCAGUGAGACAACAACUGAGCAAAAAGAACUAGACGAGGCUUGCGCUUGGAAAGUCACGGUAGGAUUGGACCUGCCGGCCACAUGGCUCAGGGAGUAUUGACGGAUUUGCACAUUGGCAGGAAACUCUCCCGUUUGGGAUUCUUUAAAUGGGGCACAGAAGGCCACUUGUUUGCAUUUCUGGGUAAAAAACAGUCAUCCCCCAUGACUGCCUGCAUCGGGUUUGUCUUGUGCCAAAGUUACUCUUCCUUUGUUUUUACUUUGCCUUGAUUUUUAGCAUUAGCUGGUAGUUUGGCUUGGAAAUGUCCUGGAUAGCCGAUUCCCUAAGAAACUGAAACAUUUAAUAUUGGCUUAGGAUGUAUCAGAUGGGGCCAAAUAAAGCUUCUUUACAAUAGUAAAAGCACUUUAUACUUCACUCUCUGAGUCUUCCCAAUAAAUAACCUUGGGAGGUGCAGGGGGUGGGGGGCCCAGGAUGGGGAGGCCUGGGAGCUCCCAGGGUAGUGACAGAGUUGGGCUGAGUUCUCCAGACGCCAGGAUGCGUCGCAGCGGGGCCAGCUCAGGAGUGCUCACUCCCAGCCCUCUGGAUCUCUCUCCUGGUUGGAAUAAUCAUUACAUAUCGUAACUCUCAAAAUUUAUUCACUUAUAUUUUCAGAAUAAGAAGUGUGAAAUGUUAACAGCUCUCUGCUCUCUUACUUGUUCCCCAUUUGGGGAUCUUCUGGAGGGAAGGGGCAGGGGGAGAGUAACUUUUCUAUAUCCUUGGUUUCUAGGAACACAUCGAUUUGAAGACUCAGUAGCUGACUGGUUUUUUUUUUUCCCCCUUCAAACUGAAGUGCGAGUGUGCGUGUGUUCCACAAAAUAGCAAGUAUUUAUAGUGUUGUAAUUACAUUUCCUUGAGAAAUAUUUUCUUGUAUUUAAAAAUCUUUCUACUUCAGUAACUCCCAGCAGAACAGUGCCCAGGACAGCAUGUGCCGGUUAGUACCAGCUUUGCAGGUGAGCUGACUUCUAAACUUAGGACGACGUCUUCAUCAAUCAAACUAGUGCACAGUCCAGAAAAAGGGGUCCUUUAUCUUCUAAGUUCUGCUCCUCACCUUUCUUUGGAACCAAAAUUGCAGUGGAGUGUGAGGAAGAGCUUUGAAAGACGUGGAGUGUUGAGAUGUCUGCAUUGCACAUUCAGCCGGUUCAAAGCCAGCAGCUCCUGCCUGCAUUCUGUAGACAUCGCCCUCACACACAGUCCUCUGAUGGCUCUCAUAUAAAGCACUCAAACCGUAGGAAAGCAUGUUUUUGAGCAACGUGUCUGGGAUACUCCUCUGUGUGGUUAUUUUGAAUCUCUAUUUCUGUCAUUGAAGCAGCAAAAAACAUCAUGUGACUCAUCAACUGAUCUAAUCACACUUAAAACAGGAUGUAGAGAAAAAUCUGAUGAGAAACGUAAAAGGGCCUGUUGCCUGCCCUUUUAAAGGCAAAAUGUCUAAAAUCAUGCAAAUGUUCAAAAUGAGAGAAAUUGCAUUGUGGAAUCAAAAUAACCCAAACUCCACUCAGAAAAGUCACAAAUAUAUAGUAUACUAUCUGAUCUCAAAAGGGAAAAACGAGAUGAUAAGACCUUAAGUUUAGACUUUAUUUUCUUCUCAAGAGUGGACAUUAAAUCUAUUAACUUGCAACUUUCUGCUGGGAAGAGCAUCAAAGGUGGGCCUCCUAAAUCAUUUUUGAAAAACCUCUGUCAAGUCCAAGUGGUUCCAGGAGAAUUAUAGCCAGUAUCUUUUAAAAUAUUUCAUUUUAGUGAUAAUGUUUUUCUCUGCUUCAUUUGCAAUCAACCAGGAUCUCUAAAAGACUGCAUAAGAUAUAUGCACUUUUAUAGGUGGCUGUCAGCUACACAUAGAUUCAGCAAAUUUUUUUUAUAUAGUACCUGUUUUUAAGUUAGGCUACAUAACUUAAAGUGCACUUUACUAACAAGACUUGACAUUAGCGUCUACAAUAUGUAUAUGUAAACAAAAGCACACAAGAACUAGGCACCCUUUCUCUCUCCAAGAGUUUAAGUGGUUUCCUUAGGUUAAAGAAGGGGACAGACCAGCUAAAAAUGGUUGUACCACUCACUGUACAACCUCAUGGAAAUUCUCACUAUAAGAUUUAGAGGCAAUGUUCCCUAGCUAUAAGCCAGGGCAAGAAAUGGCGCCUCUGGAGUUGGGGAACAUUAGGGGAACAUUACAACCGGGUAGAUGCUGGUUCCCUGAAGUGUGGGGCCAUGAACAUGCAGGGACCCACGGUUUGAAUGAAACAGCUACUGAAAGCUAAGUUCAAACCACCCUUGCGUAACAAAGGAGUACAGGGUACACAUCAACACCAAUCACCCAGCACCCCACAGCGAUGGUCAUGUCACCGUGCAGCAGGUCCCUUACCCCAGGGCUGCCACAUCCACAAGCCUUGCAGUGGCAAAUACGCUGCUCCUUGGAUUUAAUGAGAUAUUUUGGUUGCUUAAUGAUGUACUGAUCAGGGAACUGUCUAAAGCUAGUAGGGCCAAGGAGUUAAUCAAAGGGCUUCGGGAAAGUGGACAAGAGCCACACACGUGAUUCUGUUCCAUGCCGACACUCAUUCAUUUAAGAAGUGUAUUCAAGCUGGAGGCUUCCAUAUCACUCACGCUUCUUGGCCUCACCUUGCUCAUCUGUCCAAUGGGAGGCUUGAGCCAUUAUUGCUAAGGCCCCUUCCUGAUCUAACAUUCUGUUUAUGAUCUAGGAUUUAGAACGUCGUAUGAGAUCCUACAAUGGAAGAAUAAAAUCACCUCAUUCUUCAUUUCAGAUCUGAACAUUAGCAGUGAUCUAGAUUUUUUUUUUUUUAAACAAAAUUAAGUGUGCUUAGAGUCAUUCCUCUACAUGGGCUGUGGCUGUCAGCCCAUAGGUUUGUCAGUUUCACAUCAAAACUGUGGGUAUAAACUGUUGAAACCAAUCACAUUAAAAUAUUUAGCUGGGCACAGUGGUGUGCAUCUGUAGUCCCAGCUACUUGGGAGGCUGAGGCAGGAGGAUCGCUUAAGCACAGGAGUUGGAAUCCAGCCUGAGCAACAGAGCAAAACCCCGUCUCUAAAAUACAAAUAAAAUAUUUGUGUAGUUUUUGAUUAAAAUUGACUACAGCGGUCAGUAUAAAAUACAUGUCGCUUUUAAGGAAGUGCUCUUUAUGUAUCUAACAGAUGGAAGUUUUUGCAUUGGUAAGAGCAUUUAUAUAUGCUUUGUUUCAGGGUUUAUGGAUUUGUAUUCAUAUAUUGUCAAAUAGGUUUCAUACUCUAAUUUUACUUUAAGUAAAGCUUAAACACUUGGCAUACAACUGA